UUGUUUUUGGCUUCUGCUACUGGAAUCAGAAGAAAACCCACUUUCUAGUCAUCACAAAGGUUCAACUUUGUGAACAGGCGUUUUCAAGAAUAUGCAGGCUUAGGGCUGCUCACGUUAAAUUUGUUUUGCUCAGAAAUUCAAAGGAGUUUGUUAAGAUAGGUGCUGCAGAUCCACACUUCGGACAUUAAGGGCAGUCCAGGCAGCACGACUUUCUCCCUGGACUCACCAGAAACACACAUUUUUCCUAUUCUGCUGUUGCUUUACCCCAUCCAGAGUUCAACUCUAGCAUCAAAAUUGUUUUAUGGAAGAAAGUGAGUGUAGACAGAGUAAGGGAUCUGAUGACCAAGUCAUGGAAUAAAUGUUUGGAGUCCACACACCACAGCAUCCUGAGAACUUCCUAGGAAUAGGGUAUAGAAACCCAGUGCUGUCAGCCUCACUCAUCCUCCUGUCCACAUGUGGGAUAUUUCAGGAUUCGGUGGCCUUUGAGGAUGUGGCUGUGAACUUCACCCAGGAGGAGUGGGCUUUGCUGGAUCCUUCCCAGAAAAAUCUCUACAGGGAAGUGAUGCAGGAAACCUUGAGGAACCUGACCUCCAUAGGAAAAAAAUGGAACAACCAGUACAUUGAAGAUGAGCACCAAAAUCCUAGGAGAAACCUAAGACUUAUAGGGGAGAGACUCUCUGAAAGUAAAGAAAGUCAUCAGCAUGGAGAAGUUUUGACACAGGUUCCAGAUGACACACUGAAGAAGAAAACUCCUGGAGUACAAUCAUAUGAAAGCAGUGUGUGUGGAGAAAUCGGCAUAGGUCUUUCAUCCCUUAAUAGGCACCUCAGAGCCUUUAGUUAUUCCAGUAGCCUUGCAAUACAUGGAAGAACUCACACUGGGGAAAAGCCUUAUGAAUGUAAGGAAUGUGGGAAAGCAUUCAGGUUUCCCAGUUCUGUUCGUAGACAUGAAAGAAUCCACUCUGCAAAAAAACCCUAUGAAUGUAAGCAGUGUGGGAAAGCAUUCAGUUUUCCCAGUUCUGUUCGUAGACAUGAAAGAAUCCACUCUGCAAAAAAACCCUAUGAAUGUAAGCAGUGUGGGAAAGCAUUAUCUUAUCUUGUAAGCUUUCAGACACACAUGAGAAUGCACACUGGAGAGAGACCUCAUAAAUGUAACAUAUGUGGGAAAGCCUUUUUUUCUCCCAGUUCGUUAAAAAGACACGAGAAAAGUCACACUGGAGAGAAACGCUAUAAAUGCAAGCAAUGUGAUAAAGCCUUCAAUUGUCCCAGUUCCUUUCAAUAUCAUGAAAGGACUCACAGUGGAGAGAAACCCUAUGAGUGUACACAAUGUAGGAAAGCCUUCAGAUCUGUCAAGUACCUGCGAGUACAUGAAAGAAAACACACUGGAGAGAAACCCUAUGAGUGUAAGCUAUGUGGUAAGGGAUUUAUUUCUUCCACUUCCUUUCGCUAUCAUGAAAAGACUCACACUGGAGAGAAACCUUAUGAAUGUAAAAAAUGUGUGAAAGCCUUCAGUUUUGUCAAGGAUCUUCGAAUACAUGAAAGGACACACACUGGAGAGAAACCCUUUGAAUGUAAACAAUGUGGGAAAACCUUCACUUCUUCCAAUUCCUUUCACUAUCAUGAAAGGACUCACACUGGAGAGAAACCCUAUGAGUGUAAGCAAUGUGGGAAAGCCUUCAGAUCUGCCUCAGUCCUUCAAAAGCACAUACGAACUCACACAGGAGAGAAACCCUAUGGAUGUAAGCAAUGUGGUAAAGUCUUUAGAGUUGCCUCACAACUUAAAAUGCAUGAAAGGACUCACACAGGAGAGAAACCCUAUGAGUGUAAGCAAUGUGGAAAAGCCUUCAUUUCUUCUAAUUCUAUUCGCUAUCAUAAAAGGACUCACACUGGAGAGAAACCCUAUAAAUGUAAACAGUGUGGGAAAGCCUUCAUUUCUUCCAACUCUUUUCUCUACCAUGAAAGGAUUCAUACUGGAGAGAAACCCUAUGAGUGUAAGCAAUGUGGUAAAGCCUUUAGAUCUGCCUCAAUCCUUCAAAAGCAUGUAAGGACUCACGCUGGCUAGAAACUCUAUGGAUGUAAGCAAUAUGGUAAAGUCCUUAGAUGGGACUCAGAACUUCAAAUGCACGGAAGGAUUCACUGCAGAGACACCUGUAAUCUCAGCAUUUUGGGAAGCCAAGGCAGGAGGAUUGCUUAAGCUGAAGAGGUUGAGACCAGCUUGGG